CUUUCCGGCGGUGCUCGCAAGCGAGGCAGCCAUGUCUUAUCCCGCUGAUGAUUAUGAGUCUGAGGCGGCUUAUGACCCCUACGCUUAUCCCAGCGACUAUGAUAUGCACACAGGAGAUCCAAAGCAGGACCUUGCUUAUGAACGUCAGUAUGAACAGCAAACCUAUCAGGUGAUCCCUGAGGUGAUCAAAAACUUCAUCCAGUAUUUCCACAAAACUGUCUCAGAUUUGAUUGACCAGAAAGUGUAUGAGCUACAGGCCAGUCGUGUCUCCAGUGAUGUCAUUGACCAGAAGGUGUAUGAGAUCCAGGACAUCUAUGAGAACAGCUGGACCAAGCUGACUGAAAGAUUCUUCAAGAAUACACCUUGGCCCGAGGCUGAAGCCAUUGCUCCACAGGUUGGCAAUGAUGCUGUCUUCCUGAUUUUAUACAAAGAAUUAUACUACAGGCACAUAUAUGCCAAAGUCAGUGGGGGACCUUCCUUGGAGCAGAGGUUUGAAUCCUAUUACAACUACUGCAAUCUCUUCAACUACAUUCUUAAUGCCGAUGGUCCUGCUCCCCUUGAACUACCCAACCAGUGGCUCUGGGAUAUUAUCGAUGAGUUCAUCUACCAGUUUCAGUCAUUCAGUCAGUACCGCUGUAAGACUGCCAAGAAGUCAGAGGAGGAGAUUGACUUUCUUCGUUCCAAUCCCAAAAUCUGGAAUGUUCAUAGUGUCCUCAAUGUCCUUCAUUCCCUGGUAGACAAAUCCAACAUCAACCGACAGUUGGAGGUAUACACAAGCGGAGGUGACCCUGAGAGUGUGGCUGGGGAGUAUGGGCGGCACUCCCUCUACAAAAUGCUUGGUUACUUCAGCCUGGUCGGGCUUCUCCGCCUGCACUCCCUGUUAGGAGAUUACUACCAGGCCAUCAAGGUGCUGGAGAACAUCGAACUGAACAAGAAGAGUAUGUAUUCCCGUGUGCCAGAGUGCCAGGUCACCACAUACUAUUAUGUUGGGUUUGCAUAUUUGAUGAUGCGUCGUUACCAGGAUGCCAUCCGGGUCUUCGCCAACAUCCUCCUCUACAUCCAGAGGACCAAGAGCAUGUUCCAGAGGACCACGUACAAGUAUGAGAUGAUUAACAAGCAGAAUGAGCAGAUGCAUGCGCUGCUGGCCAUUGCCCUCACGAUGUACCCCAUGCGUAUUGAUGAGAGCAUUCACCUCCAGCUGCGGGAGAAAUAUGGGGACAAGAUGUUGCGCAUGCAGAAAGGUGACCCACAAGUCUAUGAAGAACUUUUCAGUUACUCCUGCCCCAAGUUCCUGUCGCCUGUAGUGCCCAACUAUGAUAAUGUGCACCCCAACUACCACAAAGAGCCCUUCCUGCAGCAGCUGAAGGUGUUUUCUGAUGAAGUACAGCAGCAGGCCCAGCUUUCAACCAUCCGCAGCUUCCUGAAGCUCUACACCACCAUGCCUGUGGCCAAGCUGGCUGGCUUCCUGGACCUCACAGAGCAGGAGUUCCGGAUCCAGCUUCUUGUCUUCAAACACAAGAUGAAGAACCUCGUGUGGACCAGCGGUAUCUCAGCCCUGGAUGGUGAAUUUCAGUCAGCCUCAGAGGUUGACUUCUACAUUGAUAAGGACAUGAUCCACAUCGCGGACACCAAGGUCGCCAGGCGUUAUGGGGAUUUCUUCAUCCGUCAGAUCCACAAAUUUGAGGAGCUUAAUCGAACCCUGAAGAAGAUGGGACAGAGACCUUGAUGAUAUUCACACACAUUCAGGAACCUGUUUUGAUGUAUUAUAGGCAGGAAGUGUUUUUGCUACCGUGAAACCUUUACCUAGAUCAGCCAUCAGCCUGUCAACUCAGUUAACAAGUUAAGGACCGAAGUGUUUCAAGUGGAUCUCAGUAAAGGAUCUUUGGAGCCAGAUUUGUCGUCUCAUUAUUGUAGGAGAGAAUUUGUGGGUUGUGGCAGUAAUACAUUUCCCAUGUGUCCUGAUGCUUUCAGGAUACAUCAGUUGUUAGUGUUUAAAUUGAGUUAUUUUUAUUUUGUGCUUUUGAGAUGGAGUCUCACUCUGUCUCCCAGGCUGGAGUGCAGUAGCGUGAUCUCAGUUCGUUGCAUCCUCCGCUGCCCAGGUUCAAGCAGUUCUGCCUCAGCCUUCCAAGUAGCUGGGAUUACAGGCGUGUGCCACCACACUCAGCUAAUUUUUGUAUUCUCAGUAGAGAUGGGUUUUACCAUGUUGGCCAGGCUGGUCUCGAACUCCUGGCCUCAAGUGAUUCGCCUGCCUUGGCCUCCCAAAAUGUGCUAGGAUUACAGGCAUGAGCCACCACGCCCCGCCUAAAUUCAAAAUCUUUUUGUUUUUUUUUAGACGGAGUCUCACUCUGUCGCCCAGGUUGGAGUGUACUGGCGCGAUCUCGGCUCACUGCAAGCUCCACCUCCCAGGUUCCUGCCAUUCUCCUGCCUCAGCCUCCCAAGUAGCUGGGACUACAGGCACCCGCCACCAUGCCCGGCCAAUUUUUUGUAUUUUUUAGUAGAGAUGGGGUUUCACCGUGUUAGCCAGGAUGGUCUCAGAUUUCCUGACCUCGUGAUCUGCCCAUCUCUGCCUCCUAAAGUACUGGGAUUACAGGCGUGAGCCACCGUGCCCAGCCCUAAAUUGAAUUCUUAAAUCCCUCUUGUUCAUAAAGCAGUAUAUUUGGUUUACAGGA